GUCAGCACCAGCGCCUGGGCUGGAGGACAGAGAAGCCUUUUCCGUUGCCGGUGCCGGCCUAGCGUCCUGGAAUUACUUCAAUCAAUGGUUCCCUACGUGUCCUACCUGUGAAUCUUCAGAGUAUUAUGGGGAACCUGUAAGUUAUUUCUUGUGUUUCAAAAGCCUAUCAGAAAUCAUGCACUUUUCUAUAAUGUGACUUUAUAGGCCAAAUGAUAGGUUAUUUAACUUUUUUUUUUUUUUUUGAGAUAAGGUCUCACUCUGUCACCCAGACUAGAGUACAGUGUCACGAUCUCAGCUCACUGCAGCUUUGACCUCCCAGGCUCAGGUGAUCCUCCACUUCAGCCUCCCAAGUAAUUGGGACCACAGGUGCACACCACUACACCCAGCUAACUUUUUUGUAUUUUUUGUAGAGAUGGGGUUUCUUUGCGUUGCCAGGCUGGUCUCAAACAACUGGGCUCAAGCAAUCCACCCACCUCUGCCUCCCAAACUGCUGGGAUUACAGGGAUGAGCCACCAUACCCAGUUGCAUUAACUCAUAAUAAAAUUGAUAAUAAUGAUCAUUUAUAUAUAACUAGAAGCUUUCCCUUACUUACAUCCAAAGAUGAGCCAAUUGAACCUUCUCUGUGCAUACUUCCUUCACUUUGCUUUCCACAUGACAAGAUUUCUAAGUCUCUCUCUGAAGUAUAAACUGGAAUGCAUUCACUUCACAAAGAGUGGACUUCUUUUCUUGAAAGCUUCAAACUUGUUCUUAUCCUUAGGGUCUUUCUAAUUUGUUAUUUCCUCUGUCUGGAAUACUCUUCCUCCAGAAAUUCAAAUGUCUUGCUUCUUCCUUUUAGUAAGGUCUCAGCAGAUAACACUUUUUCCGCCAUCCCCUGUCCUAUUUCAUUUCAUCACAACACAUUAGUCCUUUCAUCUUUGUGGGGUUUUUUGUGUUUUUUUUGUUGUUGUUUUUUGUUUUUUGUUUUUUUGAGAUGGCGUUUCGCUCUUGUUGCCCAGGCUGGAGUGCAGUGGUGCAAUCUCAGCUCACUGCAACCUCCGCCUCCCAGGUUCAAGCAAUUCUCCUGCCUCAGCCUUCCAAGUAGCUGGGAUUACAGGCAUGUGCCACCAUGCUCGGCUAAUUUUGUAUUUUUAGUAGAGGCAGGGUUUCUCCAUGUUGGUCAGGUUGGUCUCAACUCCCGACCUCAGGUGUUCCGCCUGCCUUGGCCUGCCGAAGUACUUGGAUUACAGACAUGAGCCACCGCGCCUGGCUGUGUUGUUUUUUUAUUGAAAGUCUGCCAUACUAGACCUGAAGUUUUAUGUUAUCAGGGACAUUCACUUCCUUUUCCCUACUCUAUUUCCAGCAGCUGGGAAAAUCCUUGGAACAGAUUUACGUACAUAAUAUUUGAAGAAAUUUGUGAGUUUUUUGACUGCCUCUCAAUGAUAUUGUAGAUACAGUGAAUAAAACAGGCAUGAAUCCUGUCUCCAGAUUCUAUAUUUUCUAUAGUCUUGUUUAAUUGUGAGCCUAAAUAAAUCUGAAGUGAUUUAAAACUGUCAUAGAUUGGUUAUAUUUAUUUGCUUUAAUAUAUCUGUCAUUCGUCUUCAGGUAUAUGUCUUAUUCCUAUGUAAAACAGACAUUAACAUAAUUAUUUAAUCUAUUAGACCUACAAGAAUCUUCAAAAUUAUGAUUCAACUCUUCAUUUGACUGAAAAACUGACACAGGUUCUUAGAAGUGAAGUGAAAUUUUCUCAAAUCACAUGCUUGAUGACAGGGGUGGGUUUUUUUUGUUUGUUUUUUGUGUGUGUUUUUUGUUUUUUGUUUUUUGAGACGGAGUCUUGCUCUGUUGCCCAGGCUGGAGUGCAGGGACGCGAUCUCGGUUCACGCCAUUCUCCCGCCUCAGCCUCCCGAGUAGCUGGCACUACAGGCGUCUGCUACCACACCCAGCUAAUUUUGUUUUUGUAUUUUCAGUAGAGAUGGGGUUUCACCAUGUUAGCCAGGAUGGUCUUGAUCUCCUGACCUCGUGAUCCGCCCGCCUUGGCCUCCCAAAGUGCUGGGAUUACAGGCAUGAGCCACUGUACCUGGCCAACAGGGCUGGUAUUUUAAGCCAGCCUUCUAACUUUAAAUUCAGUAAUUUUUUGUUGUUGUUGUUAGCUGCUAAAUGAUGUGAAAAUAAAAUAUUUUAAAAUCCUCUUCAGUUGCAUAAACUUUUUGCCACUUAGUUUCUCUAUAGCAAAGUAUCAUCUAUUUGUUCAGUAAGUUAUUGUACAUAAAUUGGCUUCUGGUGGUUUAAAGGAUUUUAUUACAACUACCUUUUUCUUUGGUUUGAAUUUGUAGUUUUAAUUAUGAAAUGUGUCAAACAUACAGAAAAAUGUAGAGUCAUAUAAAAGAUUUAUGUGUACCCAUCACAGAGAAUAAAUAAGUGUUAACAUUUCAGGAAAAAAAGAAAAAGGCAUGAACCCUGACCUUCUGUUAUUUGUCCUUUUAUCAUCAAAUAUUUUAGCAUGCGUGGCAUAUAGUAGGCACUCACAAUAAAUGUUAAACUAUUAAGUAUCUGUAACUGGCAGUUACAUAUGUCUGAUUCAAAAUGAGAAAAUUAAUUACCAUUCUUUGUAUUCACAGAUACUUAUUUAUGAGUGACGUGCAGUUAGUUAUACAAUCAGCCUCCAUAACCAUGUGUUCCACAUACUUGGGUUUAACCAACCCCCAUCAAAAAUAUUCAAAAAAUAAAAAAUAAUGACAUUAAAAAUAAAAGGUUUUAGAAAUACAGUAUAAAAGCUAUUUACAUAGCAUUUACAUUGUAUUCAGUAUUAAAGUUGAGUAUCCCUAAUCCAAACCAAAAUCCAAAAUGCUCCAAAAUCUGAAACUUUCUGAGCACUAACUGGCACAAGGUAAAUGCUCAUUGGAGCAUUUCAGAUUUUAAAUGUUAGGAUUAGGGAUGCUAAAUCAGUGAAUAUAAUGCAGAUAUUCCAAAAUCUUUUUUAAAAAUCCAAAAUCCAAAACACUUAUGGUCCCAAGCAUUUUAGAUAAGGGUUACUCAAGAGUAUGAGGGUAUGUGCUUACAUUAUAUGCAAAUACAGUUGUACCAGUCCUGAGGUGAGUAUUCAUGGGGAAUUGAUACCAGGACCCCAGAGGAUAUCAAAAUACACAGAUGCUCAAAUUCUUUAUGUAAAAUAGGAUAGCGUUUGUAUAUAAUCUGUGCACAUCCUCCCAAAUAUUUUAAAUCAUCUCUAUACUAAUAAUAAUACAAUGUAAAUGCUGUGUAAAUAGUUGUUAGACAAGAAAUAAAAAGUCUGUACAUGUUUAGACCAUCAAUUUUUUUCCAAAUAUUUUCAGUCCCAGGUUGGUUGAAUCCACAUACAUGGAACCCAUGGAUACAGAUCAAAUGCUUUAUUACACAACACCAUUUUACAUAGGGGAUUUGAGCAUCCUCUGGUUCUGGUAUUUGUGGGAGGGUCCUGGAACCAAUCCCCCACAGAUACUGAGGGACAGCUAUAUGCUUUUCUUUAAAAUUCUGAAAAGUCUUGGCUCUAGCUAAUGUUAGUUGAUUUCUAUGAAGGCCAUAAUUUGUAAUUUUGCUGAGGCUCACAUUCAGUCAACCCAUCCAUUUUCUGUAUAAGCACUAGUGAAAGUCACUUAGCCAGUUGGCUCUACACCCAAAUCUCAAUAACCUUGUGCUCUAAUCUCUCACAUAUUGCAUCUUGACUGCAUUGUGCCAAGAGGUAUUCACUAAUGUAGAUACUCUGUAAGGCUUCAAGUUUGUUUGUUUGUUUUUACCUCCAAAACAUCUAAAACUUUUACCUCUAAAAACAUUCAAGGUCAAGUGAAUUAUUUAGUGAACUGUCUUAAAUGCCAUUGUCAUUAAGGUAUAUUUGUGCGUGUGUCCAGCACAUUCAUUGGGACUGACUGUGUGACAGACAUUGUGCCAGGUUCUGGACUGACCCAGGAAGCUCACAACUUUGAGUGAUACAUGUCAAUAAUAAAUACAUGUAUCUUCUGUUACUUAGCAGAAAAGAGGAAGCCCUAACAGCUUGCAGAAGUCAUAGCAGUGAGGGAAGGAAUGCUCUACAGAAGAUGACAGAUAAGAUGAGUGAUGUUAUUAAUAACUUGUGUAUCGGCACAGAGACAUUAUGGUUUUUGUCAUGUUUGGGGCACUACAAGUCACUGGACUACACACUGGAUGCAGUUGAGAGAAUAGUUCAGAUGAGGUUGAAAACAAAAGCAAGGAUUUUUUUAAUAGUCAAAAGCUUCAAAAUUAUUUUAAGCAAGAAUAUGUAUGUGAAACAAGUUUUUCUUGAGAAAUUGCAGUAUUUUCUUUAGAAAUAUAUACUUGAAUAUAUUUAAGUACUAUAAACUGUGUUUCCAAAGUCAGCUAUUGUGGAAUUGGCUGGGUGCAGUGGCUCACGCGCCUGUAAUCCCAGAACUUUGGGAGGCCAAGGCGGGUGGAUCACCAGAGGUCAGGAGUUGGAGACCAGCCUGGCCAACAUGGUGAAACCCCAUGUCUACUAAAAAUACAAAACUUAGCCUGGCGUCGUGGCAGGCGCCUGUAAUCCCAGCUACUCCCGAGGCCUAGGUAGGAGAAUGGCUUGAACAGGGGAAGUGGAGGUUGCAGCGAGCCAAGAUGGUGCCACUGCACUCCAGCCUGGGCGACAGGGCGACUCUGUCUCAAAAAAAAAAGUCAUCCAUUGUGAAUGAAUGUACAAAACGCUUAUUAAUAAGUGUAAUAUUAAAAUAUAUCUUUUCUGAAAGUUUUAGUGACAAAACAAAUUAGUUACAGAUUUAAUGUUACCAAAAUUCAUGUACAUUGAAAAUUUCGGGACAUUUUAUACUGGUGGUGGUGGGGUGGCAUCUUAGCUUGGGUUUAAAUAUCAUUAGUAAUCGGAUAGCUCUGUAGAUGAUUAUCAGUAUAUAAAGACAUCGUGAGCAGUAUUUAAUAAGAAGAGUUGCUGAAGUGACUUUUGCAGGAGGAUGAAUGCUUUUUUUAAAAAAAAAGUUUAUACGUGCCUCUUCGCUCUUCCAAAAAAAAAAGAGAGAAGAAAAAGAAGAAUAAAACGAGAGACGAAGGUGGAUAACACCUUUCUCUAGACCCCGGUGCCUCUCAUUUCUCGGGCUGCAGGCGACGGCUGCUGGGCCUGCGCGGGGUGGAGCCGACGCUGACGCGCCCUGCGCCGCAAAGCAUUGUGGGAGCUCGGGCCCGCUAGUGUCGUGGUUGGAGGCGAGGUGGGGCGGCCGUUUGUUUUCUCGUGGUCUCGAGCUCGCGCGCUCUCAUCCCCUCCCCCGCGGCGUGCGGCGGGGCGGAGAAACGGCGGCGGCGGCGGCGGCAUCGGCAGCAGUAGCAGAGGCUGUAGCAUCGGACACCCUCCUCUCUCCCGCAAUCCGGUUCCUCUUCCCCCUCCUUCUCACUGUUUGUUGUGUGUUUGAUGUGUUAAAGCAGGAGCGAGAACCCGAGCAGCGCCAUGAGCAACACUACCGUCGUCCCCAGCACUGCAGGUCCGGGCCCCAGCGGCGGGCCCGGUGGCGGAGGUGGUGGUGGCGGCGGAGGCGGCGGCACCGAGGUAAUCCAGGUGACUAAUGUCUCCCCGAGCGCUAGCUCUGAGCAGAUGCGGACUCUCUUCGGUUUCCUAGGCAAGAUCGACGAACUGCGCCUCUUCCCGCCGGAUGAUUCGCCUUUGCCAGUCUCAUCUCGUGUCUGCUUUGUUAAGUUCCAUGAUCCAGACUCAGCAGUUGUGGCACAGCAUCUGACAAACACUGUAUUCGUUGACAGAGCUUUGAUAGUCGUACCAUAUGCAGAAGGAGUUAUUCCUGAUGAAGCUAAAGCUUUGUCUCUGUUGGCACCAGCUAAUGCAGUGGCAGGUCUUCUGCCUGGUGGUGGACUCCUGCCUACUCCUAACCCACUUACCCAGAUUGGCGCUGUUCCACUGGCUGCUUUGGGGGCUCCUACUCUUGAUCCUGCCCUUGCUGCACUUGGGCUUCCUGGAGCAAACUUGAACUCUCAGUCUCUUGCUGCAGAUCAGUUGCUGAAGCUUAUGAGUACUGUUGAUCCCAAGUUGAAUCAUGUAGCUGCUGGUCUCGUUUCACCAAGUCUGAAAUCGGAUACCUCUAGUAAAGAAAUAGAGGAAGCUAUGAAAAGAGUACGAGAAGCACAGUCCCUAAUUUCUGCUGCUAUAGAACCAGAUAAGAAAGAAGAAAAAAGAAGGCAUUCAAGAUCAAGAUCACGUUCUAGGAGGAGGAGGACUCCCUCAUCUUCUAGACACAGGCGGUCAAGAAGCAGAUCGAGACGGCGGUCACAUUCUAAGUCUAGGAGUCGGCGACGAUCCAAAAGCCCAAGGCGGAGAAGAUCUCAUUCCAGAGAAAGAGGUAGAAGGUCAAGGAGCACAUCAAAAACAAGAGACAAAAAGAAAGAAGACAAAGAAAAGAAACGUUCUAAAACACCACCAAAAAGUUACAGCACAGCCAGACGUUCUAGAAGUGCAAGCAGUUUGCACAUUUGUGAUUCUAGAGAGAGACGACGACGAAGAAGCAGGAGUGGCACAAGAUCUCCUAAAAAGCCUCGGUCUCCUAAAAGAAAAUUGUCCCGCUCACCAUCCCCUAGGAGACAUAAAAAGGAGAAGAAGAAAGAUAAAGACAAAGAAAGAAGUAGGGAUGAAAGAGAACGAUCAACAAGCAAGAAGAAGAAGAGUAAAGAUAAGGAAAAGGACCGGGAAAGAAAAUCAGAGAGUGAUAAAGAUGUAAAACAGGUUACACGGGAUUAUGAUGAAGAGGAACAGGGGUAUGACAGUGAGAAAGAGAAAAAAGAAGAGAAGAAACCAAUAGAAACAGGUUCCCCUAAAACAAAGGAAUGUUCUGUGGAAAAGGGAACUGGUGAUUCACUAAGAGAAUCCAAAGUGAAUGGGGAUGAUCAUCAUGAAGAAGACAUGGAUAUGAGUGACUGAAUAUUGCCUCUGAGGGAGUCCAACUGUAUACCUGCAUCAGUGUCAUUCCUUUGUGUGAUUUCUUAAUGCUGUAUUUGUUCAUCUCAAACCUAGAUGUAUACAGCUCUGAGUUAUAAAUGGUUAUAAAGCUCCUGUUACUCAUAUUAGUUAUUUACAUCAAAAAGCUUUUAGAAAAUGGUACGAGGUAACCAAUUCUUGUCAUGGUGAAAUCUGAUUGAGUAACCAAGCAGUUUUACUAUUCUGGUGCUGCUUCAUAACAAAAAUGAAAAGCUGCAUGCAUCUACAGCAGGCAUGGAUUGUUUAUGUCGUAUGAUAUCCUUUAUUAAGUAAGUUCACUUAUAGUAUUUCUAUAAUUUGAUUCAUUGCCGUAAUAGAGCCAUGUAGGAAAUGCACUGAUUGCAUGUUAUUGUGGCAAGAAUAUCCUAAAUGUCAUUAAAAUCCUCCAACAUGAUGGAUCUACUUAUGGUCUUGUUUGUUGACAUGACAAAUUAACAUUCUUAUAGUUACAUCUGGAAAUGAGCAUUUGAAAUAGAUAAUCCUUUAAGCCUUGUGGCAAAAUUUUUGUGGCUUUUGUUUAACUUUGAAAGGUUAUUAUGCACUAACCUUUUUUGGUGGCUAAUUAGGGUUUAAAUACAGAAACAAGAUUUCAAAUAAAACUGUCUUUGGCAGUGAGUAAAUAGCAUAUUUUGAAGUAGAGUUGUAUACUUUUUCAUAAGAUGUUUGGGAAUUUUUUUCCUGAAGUAAUAAUUUAUUCCACAUCUACAUCAGUGAAAGCUAUCUACCUAUCCUGAGUCUAUCUUAAAGGAAAAAAAGAAAAAAACCUUAUCUCUUGCCCUUAUUUUGAAUUUUCCACUCUUUCAUUAAUUUGUUUUAAGCUCCGUGUUGGAAAAAAGGGGUAGUGCAUUUUAAAUUGACCUUCAUACGCUUUUAAAAUAAGACAAAUCUACUUGAUAAUGUACCUUUAUUUGAUCUCAAGUUGUAUAAAACCAAUAAAUUUGUGUUACUGCAGUAGUAAUCUUAUGCACACGGUGAUUUCAUGUUAUAUAUGCAAAGUAGGCAACUGUUUUCUUAGUUACAGAAGUUUCAAGCUUCACUUUUGUGCAGUAGAAACAAAAGUAGGCUACAGUCUGUGCCAUGUUGAUGUACAGUUUCUGAAAUUGUUUUACAAGACUUUGAUAAUAAAACCCUUAAACUUAUGUUCAUGUUCCUGUAAAACCGUAUUUGUAUUUAUUUACGCUACUGAAUGUAUGACAUUUACCUCAUUCAUUUUACAAAUUCUUUCCCUUUCUGUCCACAUAUUUCAGUAUAGUAAAAAGAGGAAGUCUAUCACUGUAGUGAUAAUUGCCAUCAAAAUUGUCAAAAAUGAUUUAAUUUCUAUCCAAAAUAGUCCUUUUCUUAGCUUAGUAUCAUUUUAUUGCUUAUUUUUUGUGUGGGAAUGGGGUUGGAUAAAGCAAUGAACUUUAGUAUAAACAAAUCCCACCUAUAUCUAGCAAAUUUAUAUUUUCGGUGAAAUACAGAUAUUUGCCUUUCUGGAGUAGUAUAGAAGCUGUCAAUAUGUAUCUACUGUACAGUACUAAAUAGUAUUCAUUUAUGAAAUGAGUAGUGUUUGGGUGGCUGGGGUUAAGGGAAAAUGAGACUUGGAAUUGUAGCUUUUAUCCAAGUUUUGAGUAUAAAUAGGGUUUUGUUUUGUUUUUUUUAACCUAAAAACUGAAAUGCCAUAUAGAAAAACAGCAUUGUUUUUACAGUUUGUAGUAAGUAACUUUUUAAAGAUUUUAUCAAAAAGAAUUGUCUAUAGUGAGUAAAAGAAGUUCUAAUAAUGGUCCUAAUCACUGCAUUUUUAAAAAACAAAGUUCAACACAAAUGACAUUUGUUUUAAACUUUAGUAGAUAAAAGGUGAACCAUGUGACAUGGGCAUUUUUGUAAGUCAAAAACAAAUUUCACAUAUGGUAAACCUAAUAUUCACAGUGUGUUCCCUCACUUGUAAUCUCUGAAUACAAAUAUACUAGCUUUUCUAAAGGGAAUCAUUUUUUUAAAAGUAGUGCCACUGACAAGAUGCUACAGUGAAGAUUAUCCAUUCUUAGGAUAUUUAUUUUCAGUGAACAUUUUCUGCACAAAGGUAGUGUUGCACUGGGACACAAGCCUUUUAACAGAUAACCAGUUGAAAUCAAACACUGCCUCCACACCGAGUUCUGUUGUGUAUUUGAUAGUAAAUUGAUUUAAAAAUAAAAGUGGUUUUUGUUAGAAAAA